UAGCCAGGAUGGUCUUGAUCUCCUGACCUCAUGAUCCACCCAUGUCAGCCUCCCGGAGUGCUGGGAUUACAGACCGCACCUGGCCGUUAUUCUGCUUCUUAAAGCAAUGUUCCCCUGCCUGUCUCCAAUAUCCUGUCUCAGAACUGUCAGCCAGACUGUGCCAGGCCUGGGGCCCUCCUUGGUGCCAGCACUAGCAGGGGAAAUCAGCUGCAGGUCUCCAAGGUCUUCCUGGCCUCAUUCCUUGCUGGCUCCAAACCCGGAAGUGAUGAGGAGAGGGAGGGGACUGAGGCUGUACCUUCUGGGGGAAGCACAGUUUGGAGGCACUUUCGGUCCAGCUCUCCUCUCAGCAGCCCAUUCCAGCCUUUUCCUUGUGCUGGGGUGUUAGCCCGGGCUUCCUCACCUCAGAAGGGACAGUACCCAUGGGCGGGUGGCUCGGACCAUGCAGGGCUUGGCCCUGCUGUGGGCAGUACGAGGUCAUCAGUAGGUCCCAUGGGCAUUUCAGGACGGGCUUGGGAAAGUCACUGGGCUGGGGUGGAUGCUACCUCCCUCACUUUAGGCCACAGGGCUGGCCUGAGGAGCAGAGGAGGAGGAGGCCAGCCUCAGGUCCCAAUCGCUGCAUCACCAAUGUGUUGAGUGGAACCCGAGUGUUUAUUUUGUAGAAGCUGCGUUGGAGAGAGCUGGGCUCCUGGCAUUUGUGGAGCCUGUUGCUUUCCAGGAGGAUGGUCUGGGAGGAGAGCCAGGAGCUGCUGGCCGGCAUCCAGGUCUGGGCUGGAUUACAUGGCUGGGCUUGCCCAGAGCAGUGAGCCCCACCCACCACCAGCCCAUUCCUGAAGGGACAGGGAAGGAGGUCAUGGAGGGUGGGGGUGUUCCCAGAGGAGCAGCAAGCACAACCUGGGCCUCCAAAGCAGGCUGCAUGGGGGCUCCACCUUGUCACUUCUGGUGGAGGAGCUGGGCAGACCCCAUGCCCUCACAGUGAGUUUGGGAGAAUACACCCAGGUGGGGCCCUGCUGUGGAUAGGCAGGUGGUGCUGGGGGGUGGGGGAGUGAGGGUGGAGGUGCAGACUGGAGUCCCUGCUCCUGGCACACCAGUGCAUGGAGGGCGGUGCCUCCUCUAGCUCCCCCAAGCAGCUUGGCAGUUGGAAGCCAUGUGUGAGUGGCAUCCCUGGCCCUGCCUGCGUUGGGCGGGGGGGUCAUCAGACUACAACUCUGGAGUCAGGCUUUAGGUCCUCACUCUGCUACCUACAUGCUCUUGUGACCCUGGGCAAGUUGCUUAACCCCCAAGAACCUUUAAUUUCUUAUCUGAAACUGCAGAGAUAACGCCCCGCUCACUGGGCCUGUGGGAAGAUUGAGGAGAUCAGACCUGCCCACAUGUAGGCUGCCAUCUCAUACAGGGCUGUGGCGGUGGGCGAGGUGCAGCCUUCGCCCCUUGGAGCUAUCUCUUGUCUACCAAGGCUUCCUCAGGGAGGACUCCAGGCCAUGGGGAUAGGAUGAACAAAGUCCUGGGCUUGUGACUGUGCAGGGCUGGUUGGUGUGUCCAGGGGCUGGGCCUUGGGGCACUUCUGGAUACUGGCUGCCUCCUGCCUGGCUGCCUUGUGCCUUCCAGGCAGUCUCUCCCAUGGCUUAGGGGCUCCUGGGAAGAGGCUGAGCUCACACAGGGCCACCCGUUGCAGCUGCAUCUGUCCCGGCCACACCUGAAGUAUGAGAGUCAUGGCCUCCAGAAGGAGCCAUGUGGAGGCCCAGCACCUGGAGCAGUUCUGAAUGCCUGGCUUCUUGGAGGCCAAGGUUCUAGGCAAGGUGACCAGGCAUUGAUGCACCCCCAGGAAGGCCACGCGCUCAGGAGCCCCCCCCGCCGCUGGCUGCUGCUCACAUGGUGUCUGGGCCCUUGGCACUCCGGUGGUGCGCGUGGGCAGGGCGCGGGGACAUGGGGCCCGACAUGGAGCUGCCCAGCCACUCGAAGCAGCUCCUGCUGCAGCUGAACCAGCAGAGGACCAAGGGCUUCCUGUGUGACGUCAUCAUCAUGGUGGAGAACUCCAUCUUCCGGGCCCACAAGAACGUCCUAGCCGCCAGCAGCAUCUAUUUCAAGUCCCUGGUCCUGCACGACAACCUCAUCAACCUGGACACAGACAUGGUCAGCUCCACAGUGUUCCAGCAGAUCUUGGACUUCAUCUACACAGGCAAGCUGCUGCCCAGCGACCAGCCAGCCGAGCCCAACUUCAGCACCCUCCUCACUGCCGCCAGCUACCUCCAGCUGCCCGAGUUGGCAGCCCUCUGCCGCCGCAAACUCAAGCGAGCCGGCAAGCCCUUUGGCUCUGGGAGGGCGGGGUCCACUGGCAUGGGGCGGCCCCCCCGCAGCCAGCGGCUGUCCACGGCCUCUGUCAUCCAAGCUCGGUAUCAGGGGCUCGUGGAUGGGCGCAAGGGGGCCCACGCCCCCCAGGAGCUCCCCCAAGCCAAAGGCUCAGACGAUGAACUCUUUCUUGGUGGCUCUAACCAGGAUAGCGUGCAAGGUCUGGGCCGGGCUGUCUGCCCAGCUGGCGGGGAGGCGGGUCUGGGGGGCUGCAGCAGCAGCACCAACGGGAGCAGCGGGGGCUGCGAGCAGGAGCUGGGCUUGGACCUGUCCAAGAAAAGCCCACCCUUGCCCCCUGCCACCCCAGGUCCCCACCUCACUCCCGAUGACGCAGCCCAGCUGAGCGACAGCCAACAUGGCUCGCCCCCUGCGGCCUCUGCUCCUCCCGUUGCCAACAGUGCCUCUUAUUCUGAGCUGGGGGGCACCCCUGAUGAGCCCAUGGAUCUGGAGGGGGCCGAGGACAACCACCUGAGCCUGCUGGAGGCGCCUGGUGGGCAGCCUCGGAAGAGCCUCCGGCACUCCACUCGGAAGAAGGAGUGGGGCAAGAAGGAGCCUGUGGCUGGCUCCCCCUUUGAGCGGAGAGAAGCAGGGCCCAAGGGUCCCUGCCCGGGAGAGGAGGGUGAGGGGGUCGGGGACAGGGUUCCCAAUGGCAUCCUGGCUAGUGGGGCUGGCCCUAGCGGGCCCUAUGGGGAGCCCCCCUACCCCUGCAAGGAGGAGGAGGAGAACGGCAAGGAUGCAAGUGAAGACAGUGCGCAGAGCGGGAGCGAGGGGGGCAGCGGCCAUGCCAGCGCCCACUACAUGUACCGGCAGGAGGGCUACGAGACGGUGUCCUACGGGGACAACUUGUAUGUGUGCAUUCCCUGCGCCAAGGGCUUCCCCAGCUCUGAGCAGCUCAAUGCGCACGUGGAGACUCACACGGAGGAAGAGCUGUUCAUCAAGGAAGAGGGGGCCUACGAGACAGGCAGUGGGGGUGCCGAGGAGGAGGCCGAGGACCUGUCAGCACCCAGUGCGGCCUACACGGCUGAGCCCCGGCCCUUCAAGUGUUCGGUCUGCGAGAAGACCUACAAGGACCCAGCCACGCUGCGGCAGCACGAGAAGACGCACUGGCUGACACGGCCCUUCCCCUGCAACAUCUGUGGCAAAAUGUUCACGCAGCGCGGCACCAUGACGCGUCACAUGCGGAGCCACCUGGGCCUGAAGCCCUUCGCCUGCGAUGAGUGUGGCAUGCGCUUCACCCGUCAGUACCGCCUCACGGAGCACAUGCGUGUGCACUCGGGCGAGAAACCUUACGAGUGCCAGCUGUGCGGGGGCAAGUUCACCCAGCAGCGCAACCUCAUCAGCCACCUGCGCAUGCACACCUCCCCCUCCUAGAAGCCAAAGACCCGCGGGCGCCCUCUGCCACCUUGCUCCCCGGGAACCCAUGGAAGGAGAAGCGAGGUGAUGCAGCAGCAGGGGCAAGACCCUGGGUCCAGUGGAGGCUCCGGGUGGCCCCUCUGGCCCCCACUGCCCACACCCAGAGCUUUAAUGGACAGUCCGUACCAAGCAGAGCCGAGAGGAGGGAAGCCAGGGGUCCCAGCCCGUCUACCUCCCCAUCCCACCCAGGCCCCCAGCUCCCCGCGGGGGCCACCGCAGGGCCUGUGGGCUGGGUCACGUGGGUCUCGCUGGGACCUGGUCCCUUUGUUGCAGGCGGCUUGGAGAAAGGGCAGUGGGACGCUGGCCACGGCCAGGGUGGUGUCGGGAGCAGGCCUCACCCCGCUGGCCGUGUCUGUGUGUGUGCACGUGUGCUUGUGUCUGUGCGGGCGCGUGCAGCCCUGGUUCUGCAGGGAACAGGUGCUGGGGGUGCAGAUCCCUCCCUCCUUGAGCCAGGGUGGCACUGUUCACUGGCGCUGGGACAGUCAGGGUGACCCCACCGCCUACCUCUCUACAUCUAAAGAGCCCUCUGGGCCUGUGUUGCUGUUAUUCCUACUGAUCUGUUCCUCUGUUUUUCUUUUUGAUUUUUGUUUUUUAAACCAAAACAGACAAUAGCUUAUUUUCUUUCCGCCCCCUCCGGGGCUGAGCCUGGGUCUGAAGACUGAAUGUAACAGGGGCCGCUGGCACUCCUGCGCGUCCCCCGGCUCUGGCGCUGCAGGGGUGUCGGCGCGCCACCUCUCCAGGCCCCAGAAGCCCUUCUUGCCCAAAGGCUUCCCUGGUCCCUGAGCCCUGCCUCGGCUGCCUCAGGGGAGAGUGCUUUUCCUGUAGUUUCCAAGGAAUAUUCUUUGUUUAGAGGUACUUGUUUUUUAUUAAGAGAAAAACCAGUGUAACGUUUAUGUGACUGUUUGAACUGGAAGGUCUGGGGUUCCGGGGGGUGGGGGGAGGCUAGACUCAAUGCCGGGGCCGUCGGUACUCUUGUUUUCAUUUGUGUGUGCGUGCGUGUGUGUGUGUGUAUGUGCGUAUGUGUGUGUCUAUGUGUGGUGUGUGCCGUAUGCAUGGGCAGAUGUUUCGCUUUCCCUCCUUCCUCGCUGAACAAGGUGGAGACUUCUGACCUUUUGCUACCUCUUGAAUUCAUGACAACGAUAUGUUGGUGACUGGCAGUGGAAGCCCUUGACACUCUUGUUUUCCUUCGCUUAGCACCUAGGAAGUCGUGUGCAGGAGCCAGCAGGGCGCCAAGUGGCCCAGUGCCUGCAGCUCACCUGUGGGUUUUCCCUUUGAGCCUUUGGCCACAUCCACCUCGAGGGGACCCUGGCACCCCGGGCACACAAACCUCUGUGGUAUAGGUGAGGGGUGUGAGGCCCCAGCCUGGAGCCAGGCACUGGGUGCUGACAGGGGAACCAUGAGGAGGGUGGCAGGUCUUUGCAGCUCCCGGCCAGGGUGAGGCGGAAGUGAGCCCUCAUCCUGCCACUCCUAUCCUCCAUUCCUGCAAGAGUUUUAAGCUUGAGAGAGCUGACCACAGGGCCCCCCGGGGAACAGGGAUGGCACUUCCCUGAGCAGUCCUGGCCCCCGGCCACUGUCUCGGGGCCCACCUCUCGCCCCUCAUCUUGGUAAUUAGCCAGCCUCAGAUACUUCUGUGGGCCCUGAAGUGGGCUCUCAAGGUCAGACCAAGGUUGCUGAUCUCAGUCCCACUGUCUUCAGCCAGCUGAAGCUGUGGGGCUGGGCUGGCAGCCUUUAUUGUCAUCUUGCUUCACCAUUUUUUUUUCUCUCUCUUUUCAUUCUAUUUUAAGUUUAGACCAAAAAAAUACAGAGUCAUCCCCUACCCCCACCCCUCUAGAGACCCUCCAGCUAAAAACAGAGCCUGAGUUCAGGGACCCAAGUGGUGAGCGGCGUCUUUUGGGGGUGAGGGAGCUUGGGUAGAUGAGGCUCCUGGCUGAGCCCUCCCUGUGGUGAUCCCAGCCUAAGAUGGCCCCUCUUCCCUCCUGGUGGGAGACAGAGGACUGGACCCUGGGUCUCAGGUUCCAGCAAGUCAGGCUAGGGACCUGGGGGGAGGAGACCCAUGGACUUCACCCAUACUCAGUGAGGGGGCUCCUGCCGUCCUGACGCCACCCCGCCCCAUCAGCACUUAAGCCACAUGACACAAAGUCUGUACCGCACGGGAAAUGUUCACGCGCCUGGCCGUGUGCAUGGCCUCCCGGGCUGUGGGCAGCCGCAUCUGUGAGGUGACUCGUGAAAGUAGGUGAUUCCUUUGCAGAACUUCAGGGACUGGGAGCAGAGGCCCCUCACUCAACGACGUUUGUGCGACAUAGUAUUGUAUCCACCUUAGUAUUGUAUCGAGCCUUUUCUGUGUUUUAAUGAGAAAGCAGAACACUAGUUUCCUAUUUAAGACUUUAAGGGUUUGUGGGGCGGGGCGGGAUUAACACAACAUUUGGCUUUGUUUUCUUUUUCCUUUGAUUUCCACAUCAGGUGUGUGCGAGUGUGUGUGUGUGGAGAUGUUAAGAGCCUCACAAGGAAACUGGGUUAUUGGAGGCCAAGGCGGCUUACAGUUCUCUGCGUUCGUCACUUAAUUCCUGAAUGUUUCAGAGAAACAGGAAUCAGAAAAUAGCAGAUAUCAUGUAGGAAAGAGAGGAUAAACAAAGAAAAAAGAAAAAAAAAUAAGCUCAUACCCAAAUUCACAAAGCCUAUUUUUUAAACCAAAGCACAUUUUGAAUGAGUAUGGAACCUCCAUGGGCUCAGAAAAAAGAUGCUAAUAUAUUUAUCUCAUUGUUUACAUAAGCUUUUACAGUUUCAGACCUCAGCAGCUGUAAGGCCAGUCCAGGGAACCCUCCCCUGCUGCUGGAAACCCUUCUGAGUUGGCCCUGGAGUGGCUCACGGGCAGAGAAGGGUAGCCCUGGGGCUGGGGGAGGGAUUGGAAGCCUCCCUGGAGUCACCUGAGCCCUCGUCCCCAUUCCCAGGGCCCCUCCAAGCCCAGCUGGCACCAAAGAGCUUGGGCCCGUGCUGACCAGCCCCCAAGGCCCUCUGGCCGGACCAUGCUGGUCCUGACCAGCUAGCCUACGCGGGGAUGGCCGUCAGUUCUGGCCACAGGACCCGAGUCUGGGCUUGGGUCCCCCUGCUGCUCUGCCCGUGACCCUUGGGGAUGGGUUGAUGCGAGGGUCCCACUCAAGCCAAAAAGCCGGGACCUUUGCGCAGCUCUGUCGACUCUGGUGGGUCCCCACUCCUGGGGCCCCCUAACCCCACCCCAGGCAGCGGAAGGGGCUGACUGGGUCUGGUCCUUACCAACAUAGACGGUGCAAACACUCUUAACAGUGUUGUUUUUGUAUCAAUAUGUUUGUGCAGUGAUGAAUGUAUUUAUUUCUCAGACUUGGGGCGAGUGAGCGGGUGGCAGGCCGGGCUCCGCCACUGCAUGCUCCCGCCGGACCGAGCCCCAGCAAGGGCUCCUCCAGGAUUGCAAAAAAAAAAGGAAGAGAAAAGAUGAACCUUUAAGCAAAUAAGAAUCUCAGAGACUCGCAGCAUAGCCAUACACCUCAGCCUGUGAAAUGAACGAUCCGGACCCUCACCAACUUUCCCCACCUCAGGCAGCCCUGUGUGUUUACCGUUCAUCACCACUCGGGGGCACCGGGCCGCCCACCCACUCCCAAAAUCCGUCAGUAUUCACUGGACCUCAGGCCCUGUGCAGGAGUGCGAUCCGGGCUGGGCCGCUGGGCAGGCUGACCCCCUGCCCUCCUGCGGCCAUCCUGAGUUGGGGUGAGGCCUGGGCAGCCGGAGGGCAGGGCUCAGGGAGCAGGAGGCUGCAUCCGUCCACCCCCAGGCGUGGGGGACAAAAGCCAAAGGUGCCAGGCCUUAGAGCAGACAAGGGCUCUCAGCCCUGGCAUGCCCCCUAAAGGGACCAAGGUCCUCCUAUUUCCCAGAACCCCGUUGGGGCAGAUGUUACUGAACCUGUGAAUCAGACGCCAGGAGUGAGGGCUGGGGAGGGACCUAACUGGAGCCUCAGUCUGACAUUCCACGCCGGGGUGGGGGUGGGCAUGAGCGGUGGGAACUGAGGCUGCCCAGGACCCCCUUCCUAGGAUGCCCCGGCUUCAGUCACCCCACUUUAACUUUCUACCAGGACCCCCUCCCCCUACCUCACCUUGCUAUUUAUUGCUGUAAUUUAUUGACCUCAAAAAUGCUGCAUAACAGACCUCACUGGGGCAGGGAGGAUCCCCAGGGCUCCCACCCUCCACUUGGCGGGCCCCGUGGGGCCAGGUGCUGAGGGGAGCCUCUCUACCCCACCCAUCACUAGCUUCCCUCUGCCCUCUCCCACCCCGGGGGGGACCCAGGUUGGGCACUGGCUCAUUUCUCGCAAAUACCUCGAAGGGGAGGGGGGAGGGAUGGGGUUAUAGCUGUUUUGUUUAAUUGGAACUGGAAGAGGGAUCAUGUUUUGUUUUAUGCCCUUCCCAGAAGGGGGGAGGGACACCGGGAUCGCACUCCUGUACUGGCCACCGCCGCUGUCACUUGUCACAUUGAGUUCAUGUCCCUUGAGAGUUUGUAUAAAUUCAGGUCAGAGCUGCAGCUACACAGCUGCCCAGUGUCAUAGAAAAGCAAUUCACCAACGACUGAUCUCUCCAUUCAGAAGUGUGCAGUCUUAAAUGUACAGCGAUAAGAAACUGUUAUUUUAUGAUCUUUUCAUUAAAAGCUUGAUUGAAAA